GCACCCGGCCUCUCCUCCGCGCGUGCGGGCCCCUCGCGGCGCCUCCCGGGCUCGGGAGACCCGGUCCCGCCGCCCGCCCGGCCCGCGGCCGCCUCUUCCUCUCGCAGCCCCGCGGCGCUUGCCGCAGUCGCAGGCGGCGGAGCAGCCAGAGCGCCCCAGGUACCAGUGCGGGCGGGAGACGGAGGCGACCCUGCUGCCGGGUGGGGAGGGGGCGCCGCGCGGCCGCUGCCCUCCUCUUCCCGCGGGGCCUGGCGGCCCCGGCGAACCCCCGCGCCGCACAGGCCGUGUGCGCCGGAUCCCGGUGCCUCCGCGCCAGCUGAGACCUGCCUUUCCCAGGGGCGGCUUUGCUCCGGCCCCUAGGCCCCCGCCCUGGUACCCCACACGCCCACCGGCCGCGGGGAGCCUGCUCCGGCCCGAGAGCGCCCAUUCACCCCCCUCACCCACCUCCCCGCGUUCCCACUUCCCCGCACUCUGACCCGGCCGGACGCCCCUCCCCUAUCUUGCCGCCCGCCCCCUCCAGGGGGCUCUGCUCCCACCCCAGGGAGCCCAUCCGACCUCUGCUUGACUUCCCGCCGCUUCCUUCAGGGGCCUCGGCUCAUCGGGUGCCCCUCCCCAAACUUCCAACCCGUUUGCUCCAGGAGUUCCUGCCCCAUCCCCGAGGGCGCCCAAAUAGCCACACUGUGUCCUCCUGUAGUCGCUGCCCCCUGACCUAGCGCGACCCAGCGCCCCCGCCCAUGUCCCCCCACUCACCUCCCCCGGGGGGCGUGGUGAGUCGCGGUCUGUUCUCACGGACGGUCCCCGUCCAGCCUGCGCUUCGCCGGGGCCCUCAUCUGCUUUCCCGCCACCCUAUCACUCCCUUGCCGUCCACCCUCGGUCCUCAUGGUCCCAGAGCCGGGCCCAACCGCCAAUAGCACCCCGGCCUGGGGGGCAGGGCCGCCGUCGGCCCCGGGGGGCAGCGGCUGGGUGGCGGCCGCGCUGUGCGUGGUCAUCGCGCUGACGGCGGCGGCCAACUCGCUGCUGAUCGCGCUCAUCUGCACUCAGCCCGCGCUGCGCAACACGUCCAACUUCUUCCUGGUGUCGCUCUUCACGUCUGACCUGAUGGUGGGGCUGGUGGUGAUGCCGCCGGCCAUGCUGAACGCGCUGUACGGGCGCUGGGUGCUGGCGCGCGGCCUCUGCCUGCUCUGGACCGCCUUCGACGUGAUGUGCUGCAGCGCCUCCAUCCUCAACCUCUGCCUCAUCAGCCUGGACCGCUACCUGCUCAUCCUCUCGCCGCUGCGCUACAAGCUGCGCAUGACGCCCCUGCGUGCCCUGGCCCUAGUCCUGGGCGCCUGGAGCCUCGCCGCUCUCGCCUCCUUCCUGCCCCUGCUGCUGGGCUGGCACGAGCUGGGCCACGCACGGCCACCCGUCCCUGGCCAGUGCCGCCUGCUGGCCAGCCUGCCUUUUGUCCUUGUGGCGUCGGGCCUCACCUUCUUCCUGCCCUCGGGUGCCAUAUGCUUCACCUACUGCAGGAUCCUGCUAGCUGCCCGCAAGCAGGCCGUGCAGGUGGCCUCCCUCACCACCGGCAUGGCCAGUCAGGCCUCGGAGACGCUGCAGGUGCCCAGGACCCCACGCCCAGGGGUGGAGUCUGCUGACAGCAGGCGUCUAGCCACGAAGCACAGCAGGAAGGCCCUGAAGGCCAGCCUGACGCUGGGCAUCCUGCUGGGCAUGUUCUUUGUGACCUGGUUGCCCUUCUUUGUGGCCAACAUAGUCCAGGCCGUGUGCGACUGCAUCUCCCCAGGCCUCUUCGAUGUCCUCACAUGGCUGGGUUACUGUAACAGCACCAUGAACCCCAUCAUCUACCCACUCUUCAUGCGGGACUUCAAGCGGGCGCUGGGCAGGUUCCUGCCAUGUCCACGCUGUCCCCGGGAGCGCCAGGCCAGCCUGGCCUCGCCAUCACUGCGCACCUCUCACAGCGGCCCCCGGCCCGGCCUUAGCCUACAGCAGGUGCUGCCGCUGCCCCUGCCGCCGGACUCAGAUUCGGACUCAGACGCAGGCUCAGGCGGCUCCUCGGGCCUGCGGCUCACGGCCCAGCUGCUGCUUCCUGGCGAGGCCACCCAGGACCCCCCGCUGCCCACCAGGGCCGCUGCCGCCGUCAAUUUCUUCAACAUCGACCCCGCGGAGCCCGAGCUGCGGCCGCAUCCACUUGGCAUCCCCACGAACUGACCCGGGCUUGGGGCUGGCCAAUGGGGAGCUGGAUUGAGCAGAACCCAGACCCUGAGUCCUUGGGCCAGCUCUUGGCUAAGACCAGGAGGCUGCAAGUCUCCUAGAAGCCCUCUGAGCUCCAGAGGGGUGCGCAGAGCUGACCCCCUGCUGCCAUCUCCAGGCCCCUUACCUGCAGGGAUCAUAGCUGACUCAGAUAUCGUGUUCUGAAGGAUGCUCCACUGUUGAGUGUAACUUGUGUGUGCAGAGGAUGGGCUGGAGGACUCUGGAUGUUGGGGAGAAGGACCUCUUGGUUCAGGUUAGGAUGAAAACAAUCAUGACCUUUGCCCAUUCUGUCAGGCUGGACGGGAGGGAAUGCCCCCACCUGCAGGCAUGGAUUAAUGCUGGGCUGAACCCCUUGCUACUCACAGUGUAGUCCAUGGACAAUCGGCAUUGCCGUCACCUUUGGGAGUUUGUGAAAAAUGCACAUCUCUGCCCCUGCCCAGACCUGCUGAGUCAGAACUGCAUGUUACCAAGAUCCCAGGUGAAUCAUGUGCCCAUUACAGUUUGAGAUGUGCUGCCUUAGAUCAUCUUUAACCCUCAGAAUGAUUUGCUGGAUGGUUUUUGGACCUGUCAGUCUCCCCUCCCUGGUAUAUAUGUGGCAGCAGCUGCACCUGGGAGGCAGGCAGGCAUGCAUGUGGGCCUCUGCUCUACCACCUAUGAGCUCUGGGGCCUGACACGAGUUAUUUAACCUCUCCGAGCCUCGGUUAUCCCAUGUGUAAGGUAGAGAAAUGAUGCCUAUCUUGCAGGUUGUCUUGAGAAUUAAGACAAUGUGUGCCCAGCACCCAGUACACGGUCAGUUAAUUGGUACGUUCUGUUGUUACGACCCCCGGCUAUCCAGCCCCCUGGCCUCUCCGGCUGUGUGUCAGGAAGGGCUCUUUGCUCCCGUUGUUCUCUUUCCAUUUGCCUCCCCCUCUUCAGCCCUGGCCUAGCCUCCCAAAGCCUGACUCUGGUUCCCCAACUCCCUGUUCUGGCUCCUGGGUGGGGACCCCAUCUCUCAGGGACCCUCCCAGCUCCCAAGCUGCUGCCCUGCCUUUCCUGGGGGCAAAAGGGGCAGGUGGCAGUUUCUUUUUCAGCCUCAGAACUGGUUUUCCUCAAUCCUGGGGGGUCCUUGGACCUAGAAGGGAACAACUGAUGGGGAUAAACCCAGCCCCUUGCCCACCUGCCUCUGGCCUUCCCUGGGGUCAGUGAGAGAAAUGGGAAUGGUAGCUACUUGGGUCAGCAGAGUAGAGUCAAAGAGCUGUUCCUGGUGUGAGGUGGGGCCCACGAGGCAGGCAGGUGGACUCUGGCACAGGGGCCUUGGUUUCUGGGGGCAGGGGGUUGGGGAACUCUUGGUCGCCAGUUUACCUGCCAUAGGUCCCUUUUCAGCCCUGCCUCCCCCAAGUUCCAUCAACACAAACUCCCAGGGGGUCCUCCAUGCCUGGCCUGGCCCUCUCCUUGGUGCUGAUGAGACACAACUCUGGCCCCGGCGGCUGGCCUCUGAGGGGCCAUGGUGCUUGCGGGGCUUCCCCUAUCCCCCAGGUCUGCCCAAGGGGACUCUCAAUAAACUCUAGCUGAAGGCA